AGCGCGCGCCGCGAGCUGUCGCGUCUGGUCGUGGUCUGGCGGAGCUGCGGUUGGCUUGUGGCGUCUCCGCCGCCGCCGCCCUCCCUUCCUCUUCCCCAUCUUCUUCUCUCGGUCCCGGGAGCCCCCGCCCGGAGUGAGUAGCGCGAGGCGGUGCGAAGGGUAGGCAGCCGCUGGGAGAGGGGAGGCUGCGACCCCUAACUGUUUCGGCGCCCUGAGGUCCCGGGUCCCCGGCUCGUCACGUGACCCGGCGCGUGCGCGCGGGCCGGCACAGGCCUCACGUGCGCGUCCCCAAGAGGUCUACGGGCCGGACCUGGGCAGGGACUACGGAGCAGUCCAUGGGUCGGGGUACAGGAGGAAAGUCAAGGCACUCAAAGCCCAGGCAGGGCACUCCCCCACCCCGGUCCCCAGACCGCAGCAAAUCCCUUUCUCUGAGCCUGUUUCCCUUCCGAGAAACAGGGAUAUGGAGAGCGCCCACUUGGAGGAUGGAUGGGAGGAAUCGGUAAAAUCGGUAAAAUGCCCAGUUCAGAGCCUGGCACAGUUAAGUGCCCGCUGCACAGAAGUUGCUGUCGUAUUUAACCUUGGGUGCCACCCGAGCGCCAGCCCGACACAGGUGCAGCUCAAAAAAGACAGCCCGAGAGCCCUUGCGGCCAAGGUCAGCCUGUCUGCAGGGAGGCUGCCAUAUCGAAAAGCCCAGACUUUGCUGCGCACCAACUGUGUGAUCUCUCCCUCUGGACUUUGGUUUCUCCUCUGUACUAUAAGUGAUUGCCACAACUGGUGUCAGAGGCCCUGACAGCGGGGAGGGACAGUGUAACCGGUGGUUGUGGUGUGUAGAAUGAUUGCCCAGUGAGAUGGGAUGAGCCUCUGGGAGGAACCAGGGCUGGUAUAAGGAGCCUGGAUUCCCUCCUUAAUUCUGUUCUCGGCUUCCUGUUUGUAUGUUUAAAGACACGUCACUUCCUUUAGUGUGCUGGUUUUUCUCUAUGUAAACUGAGGACUGUGCGGGGGUUGGAAGGAUGCAUGGAGCGUUUUGGUGGAGGCCGGAAGCCCUAGGAUCACAAGGAUGGCAUCUAAAAAAUCUCGGUGGGGGUUCUGUGCUUAUAGGCAGAGGAAGCUCACUCCCCACUCUGGCUGAUUUGCAGAGCUGUUUGAGUCUGCUGGCUUGGCCGCCCAGCAUACCAGUAACAGUCCCCUAGGUGUGUCCAAUACAGCUUCUGUGGCAUUCUAAGGCAGUUUUCCCAUUUGAUCCUCAUAGUGGGCAGAGUUGACAAGAAUCUCAUUUGACAGAGAUUUCUAAGCUCAAGAGAGAAUAUGUGCCCGGCACUGUGCAAAGCACUUUAAGCUUUUCAUAUGCACUUUUAAUCACAGCCUUUCUGUAAAGUCGGUAUUACUGUUCCAUUUUAUAGGUGAACUGAGGAAUGGUGAGGUUUAAUGUCUUGUCUGUGCUUACACAGCAGGUGUGCAGAGCCAAGAUUCAGAUCUGGUUCAUCUGGCUCCAUCAGAGCCUUUGUUAGUUUUUAAAUGUAUCCCCUGUUUUGUCUUCUUCCCUCCCUUUCUCACUUCCUUCUUUUUCUUAGAGCACUCUGCCGUUUGCAUGUGGCCUGCUGCUGUCCACAAAGAUCCAGGGAGGAUGGACUCUGUCCACUAGGCUGCUAGAGGGUGGAGGUAACUUUUAGGCAGGCUUUUCCGUAGAGACUUACGUGAGGAGGAUGAGAUGACUGCAAAAGUCUGCCGGUGACAGUUUCAGCACUGUUUUCUUCCAUGGGUCGUGGGAGAAGAGAUGCAGUACCUUGGGUCUGAACACCUUGGCGGGGAGGAGGAGGCAGCAGCCAGGUGACUGUGAAGGAUGUAGGAUCACAUUUACUGGCUGAGCAGCCAUUUACCAGGCAUGAGGGGUUUGUCUUCCUCUCUGAGCUAGCCUAGAGUGCACACAAAGCCCGUGUGCUCCUGGCCCCCUCCCAGGCCCUUCAGCCACAUACGGCAUCUGUGCUCUGGAGCAGAGUGUAGCAGGACCACCUGCUGUUGGCUGACUGACCUUGCUGUUCCCUCAGACUCUUAGGGACCUCCUCCUGCCCCACUCCAAUCUGGACACCACGAGGCAAAAUGUAGCCAGGACCCCAGGAAUCCCGUUUAUUAAUGAAUCAGCUGUUAGGGCAGAUGUCAAAGUCAGGCUUGCUAUUUCCCGGCCAGGAUGUGCCUCCCCUGGCUUGUUCCCAGAAUUUGCGUGUAAGUGGAAUUCUUGUAAAUUAGAUUAUUCAGGGGACCCUGACAUUUAAAGGAAUCAUGUUACAAGGCUUUUGGUAAAGCACAGAAUUAUAUUGUCGGUAGCAGCCUUCAGGCCUUCAGUAUUUACCAGUUCUGAAUGGUUGGACUUUUGUCUGUAGGAUUUUCUUAGAGUGGAAAAUGGCUAUAGCUGCACAAAGCCCAUUCUUGCAUUAUUUGGCAACCAGUUAGUCAAUGCCCACCUGGUAUCAGGCACUGGGCUAAUGGUGUACAAGGUAAUGUCUCUACCCCCAGGAAGCUGCAUGCUGGGAGAGGAGACGGAUGGAGUCCAGCCUGGAGAGUCGCGGUUGCUGAUCGUGGUGCUUGAGUAGAGCCGUGGUUGGUGACAGCAUGACGAGCGAGGUGAUAGAAGACGAGAAGCAAUUCUAUUCCAAGGCCAAGACCUACUGGAAACAAAUCCCACCCACGGUGGACGGCAUGCUUGGGGGGUAUGGCCACAUCUCCAGCAUCGACAUCAACAGCUCCCGGAAGUUUCUGCAGAGGUUUUUGAGGGAAGGCCCGAACAAGACAGGAACGUCCUGUGCCCUGGACUGUGGAGCUGGCAUUGGGAGGAUCACCAAGCGGCUGCUCCUGCCGCUGUUCAGAGAGGUGGAUAUGGUCGACAUAACGGAGGACUUCCUGGUUCAAGCCAAGACCUACCUGGGGGAGGAGGGCAAGAGGGUGAGGAACUACUUCUGUUGUGGGCUCCAGGACUUCACCCCGGAGCCGGACUCUUACGACGUGAUCUGGAUCCAGUGGGUGAUAGGCCACCUCACCGAUCAGCACCUGGCCGAGUUCCUGCGGCGCUGCAAGGGCAGCCUCCGCCCCAACGGCAUCAUCGUCAUCAAAGACAACAUGGCCCAGGAGGGCGUGAUUCUGGACGACGUGGACAGCAGCGUGUGCCGGGACCUUGACGUGGUCCGCAGGAUCAUCUGCAGUGCAGGCCUCAGCCUCCUGGCCGAGGAGAGGCAGGAGAACCUCCCCGAUGAGAUCUACCAUGUCUAUAGCUUUGCCCUGAGAUGAGCCGGGGCUGGCAGGAGAAACUGAGGAACCACAGUCCUGGUGGGGGGAGCUGGCAGCUGGGCAAGAUCCAGGCGCCACGCUGGCGGUUCGUGAGUGUCGAGGCACCACUAAAUAUAGCUGUCUGCCGUCCACUCAUUAUGCGGGCUCUUCUUCAAAAGGCAAGGUGGGACCCGGCGGGGAGGGUGCUGCUGAACCAGCGGUGAGGCAGGAGCCCAGACCCUGCUCUCCUGCGAGAUGGGAUUGGGUGGAAGGGGCUCCAGGGCUCCUGGUGCUCCCCAUGUGGGAAUAGGGUGGCCACAUCAGUAACCGAUUCCCUGGGCCUCCAGCCCGGCCUUCCAGCCAUGGGCCUGGCUGCCUGAAGAGGAAGGAAACCACCCCCAACUUGGUUGCUGGGGACUUGAAGACUUCAGUGUGAUCUUUACCUAGGGGAGGGACAGAGCUGGGCUGGUGGAGCCCAUGGGUGCUGCCUGAUGGUGCUGUGGGGUGGGUGCUCAUGUGCCAAGUCCUGCUUGGCAGUGGAGACCUGGGGCCCUUAAAGUGUUACAACAGCCUGCAGCAAGGGAAGUUCCCCGUAGCCUCAGUCUUCUCUGGGCUUGAGGCUGCUCCUUGGCAGGCAUUUAAAGUAAAAAAUAAAAUGGGGCUGGGCGCGGUGGCUCACGCCUGUAAUCCCA